AGACCACUCGGAGAGGAGCUGGGAAGCAGUGCAGAGAGGAGAGCGGAGCGGAGCUGCCGCUGAGCAAAGGCCUUCACCAUGGCCGAGUCCCCCGGCUGCUGCUCCGUCUGGGCCCGCUGCCUCCACUGCCUGUAUAGCUGCCACUGGAGGAAAUGCCCCAGAGAGAGGAUGCAAACCAGCAAGUGCGACUGUAUCUGGUUUGGCCUGCUCUUCCUCACCUUCCUCCUUUCCCUGAGCUGGCUGUACAUCGGGCUCGUCCUUCUCAAUGACCUGCACAACUUCAAUGAAUUCCUCUUCCGCCGCUGGGGACACUGGAUGGACUGGUCCCUGGCAUUCCUGCUGGUCAUCUCUCUACUGGUCACAUAUGCAUCCUUGCUAUUGGUCCUGGCCCUGCUCCUGCGGCUUUGUAGACAGCCCCUGCAUCUGCACAGCCUCCACAAGGUGCUGCUGCUCCUCAUUAUGCUGCUUGUGGCGGCUGGCCUUGUGGGACUGGACAUCCAAUGGCAGCAGGAGUGGCAUAGCUUGCGUGUGUCACUGCAGGCCACAGCCCCAUUCCUUCAUAUUGGAGCAGCCGCUGGAAUUGCCCUCCUGGCCUGGCCUGUGGCUGAUACCUUCUACCGUAUCCACCGAAGAGGUCCCAAGAUUCUGCUACUGCUCCUAUUUUUUGGAGUUGUCCUGGUCAUCUACUUGGCCCCCCUAUGCAUCUCCUCACCCUGCAUCAUGGAACCCAGAGACUUACCACCCAAGCCUGGGCUGGUGGGACACCGAGGGGCCCCCAUGCUGGCUCCCGAGAACACCCUGAUGUCCUUGCGGAAGACAGCUGAAUGCGGAGCUACUGUGUUUGAGACUGAUGUGAUGGUCAGCUCCGAUGGGGUCCCCUUCCUCAUGCAUGAUGAGCACCUCAGCAGGACCACGAAUGUAGCCUCUGUAUUCCCAACCCGAAUCACAGCCCACAGCAGUGACUUCUCCUGGACUGAACUGAAGAGACUCAAUGCUGGAUCCUGGUUCCUAGAGAGGCGACCCUUCUGGGGGGCCAAACCGCUGGCAGGCCCUGAUCAGAAAGAGGCUGAGAGUCAGACGGUACCAGCAUUAGAAGAGCUAUUGGAGGAAGCUGCAGCCCUCAACCUUUCCAUCAUGUUCGACUUGCGCCGACCCCCACAGAACCACACAUACUAUGACACUUUUGUGAUCCAGACAUUGGAGACUGUGCUGAAUGCAAGGGUGCCCCAAGCCAUGGUCUUUUGGCUACCAGAUGAAGAUCGGGCUAAUGUCCAACGACGGGCACCUGGAAUGCGCCAGAUAUAUGGACGUCAGGGAGGCAACAGAACGGAGAGGCCCCAGUUUCUUAACCUCCCCUAUCAAGAUCUGCCACUAUUGGAUAUCAAAGACAGGUUCCUACUACCUGCCCAGGCUGGUCUCAAACUACUGGCCUCAAGCAAUCUUCCUGCCUCGGCCUCCCAAAGUGCUGGGAUUACAGGCCUGAGCCACUGCCCCCCUCAGCCUCCCGGUUAUAAGCAUGAGCUAUCUCACCUAGCUAUGGCAUUGCAUAAGGAUAAUGUCUCGGUGAACCUAUUUGUAGUGAACAAGCCCUGGCUCUUCUCUCUGCUUUGGUGUGCAGGGGUGGAUUCGGUCACCACCAACGACUGCCAGCUGCUGCAGCAGAUGCGUUACCCUAUCUGGCUUAUUACCCCUCAAACCUACCUAAUCAUAUGGGUCAUUACCAAUUGUGUUUCCACCAUGCUGCUUUUGUGGACCUUCCUCCUCCAAAGAAGAUUUGUUAAGAAGAGAGGGAAAACUGGCUUAGAAACAGCAGUGCUGCUGACAAGGAUCAACAAUUUCAUGAUGGAGUGAAUGCCCUGCCCUGCUUCCCCACCCAAGCCAGUCUACAUUGCCCAAACAGCAAGGGUUGGAGAGUGGCUUAAGUGGAAUGCUUCAGGGGUGGUGGGUUGCAAGUGGGGGGAGCUUUGCCAACAGGAGGUUUUGAACCAUGAGGGCCCUCUGCCCAGGUGAUGGGCAUUCCCUAAGCUGCUAUGGAAUCUGCUCCCUUUGGGGUUUUGACCUGAGAUGUUUGGGAAGAGAGUGAGUAAUGAGAAGUUUCUCCUCAAAUGAAACUAGAACAGAGGAAGUAAAAGGGAGAUUGCUCGGA